AAGGGGCCCCUACAAGCGGCCACAAGGAUGGCAGGCUUCGCGGAGCUCGGGCUGUCAUCGUGGCUCGUGGAACAAUGUCGGCAGCUGGGUUUGAAGCAGCCCACGCCCGUGCAGCUCGGCUGCAUCCCCGCCAUCCUGGAGGAAGCUGUCUGAGGAUCCCUAUGGCAUCUUCUGCCUCGUCCUGACACCCACCAGGGGUCCUGCAGAAUUAAACAAGAUGGCCCCGGUGCAGUGGCUCACACCUGUAAUCCCAGCACUUUGGGAGCUCCAGGGAGCUGGCCUACCAGAUCGCAGAGCAGUUCCGGGUCCUGGGGAAGCCUCUAGGGCUGAAAGACUGCAUCAUCGUCGGUGGCAUGGACAUGGUGGCCCAGGCGCUGGAGCUCUCUCGGAAACCACACGUGGUCAUCGCCACGCCGGGGCGCCUGGCAGAUCACCUGCGCAGCUCCAACACUUUUAGUAUAAAGAAGAUCCGCUUCCUGGUGAUGGAUGAGGCAGACCGGCUGCUGGAACAGGGCUGCACUGACUUCACCGUGGACCUGGAGGCCAUCCUGGCGGCUGUGCCGGCCCGCAGGCAGACACUGCUGUUCAGCGCCACGCUGACCGACACACUCCGGGAGCUGCAGGGUCUGGCCACCAACCAGCCCUUCUUCUGGGAAGCACAGGCCCCGGUGAGCACCGUGGAGCAGCUGGACCAGCGCUACCUGCUGGUGCCUGAGAAGGUCAAGGACGCCUACCUGGUCCACCUGAUCCAGCGCUUCCAGGAUGAGCACGAGGACUGGUCCAUUAUCAUCUUCACCAACACGUGCAAGACCUGCCAGAUUCUGUGCAUGAUGCUGCGCAAAUUCAGCUUCCCCACCGUGGCUCUGCACUCCAUGAUGAAGCAGAAAGAACGCUUUGCCGCCCUAGCCAAGUUCAAGUCCAGCAUCUACCGGAUCCUGAUCGCAACAGACGUGGCCUCCCGGGGCCUGGACAUCCCUACGGUACAGGUGGUCAUCAACCACAACACCCCCGGGCUCCCCAAGAUCUACAUCCACCGAGUCGGCCGGACGGCCCGUGCAGGGCGGCAGGGUCAGGCCAUCACGCUGGUGACACAGUACGACAUCCACCUGGUGCACGCCAUCGAGGAGCAGAUCAAGAAGAAGCUGGAGGAGUUCUCCGUGGAAGAGGCCGAGGUGCUACAGAUCCUCACACAGGUCAACGUGGUGCGAAGAGAGUGUGAGAUCAAACUGGAGGCGGCCCACUUUGACGAAAAGAAGGAGAUCAACAAACGGAAGCAGCUGAUCCUGGAGGGGAAGGACCCUGACCUGGAGGCCAAGCGCAAGGCUGAGCUGGCCAAGAUCAAGCAGAAGAACCGGCGCUUCAAGGAGAAGGUGGAGGAGACGCUGAAGCGACAGAAGGCUGGCAGGGCUGGCCACAAGGGGCGUCCACCCAGGACACCGUCUGGGUCCCACUCAGGCCCAGUCCCCUCCCAGGGCCUGGUCUGAGCCCCACACGGCCAUCUGCCCAGUCCUUGACUCGUCCAUGGAGCUGAGGGUCGGAGGAACCUUCCUUGGGGGCAGCAGCCCUUCCCGGGGGCCUACCCAGUGCCCCACAGCAGAACCCGUGGGCGCUCGUGUUGUGCGGGCCCUGCUCCUCUGCCCCGAAACCACUGGCUGGUCCCUUCCCUGAGCCCUGGCCAAGAUUCAGGCUGCAGGGGAAGAAAGAACAUGACCGGGAGGUUGUGACCCCAACCCAAGGUCACCCCCCAGGGGUGCCGCAUACAGGAGGUGCUUAAUAAACGGGUCUUUUGACUUCCUCA